ACUUGCGCAUGCGCCUCGGAGCUGGCUUCAACCAGCGAAGGCUGAACCCGCUUCCAGGGUCCUCGCCGAGCUGGGAGUUAGGAUCCGAGGGGGCCAAGAGGGAUAAGAAAACUUCUCUGGGUGCCCACGUGGUACUGAGCGCCCUUGGGAGGGCUCUGGAGAAGACCAUCGCCUUCCAGGGUAGCUCCCUCCCUCAAAGGUUUGAGAUCAUGGUCCAGUUCUCGGGUCUCCCAGCCUCAGUUUCCCCAUUUGUAGGAAAGGCGUUCACAGCCUCUAUCUCAGAGGAGGCUUUGAGGAUUCAGAGAGCUCAGAAGAGGGGAAGGAAACUGAGGUCCAGAAAAGUUAUGACUCGCCCCAAGGGGAUUGCCUGGCAGGACGUGAAGGGGAAGAGGCCCACCCUGGAGUAACCCUCACUGGAGAAUCCAGAGACACGCCGCUUUUUGGAUGCCUCCUAUGCCUGGCGGGAGUCUUGUCUGAGCUGGCACCACCACACGGCCCACGACAUCUUCGCAGGGAAGCCUGUGGACCCUCUGCCAGGCUCCACAAGAGGUCAGGACAGUGCAGUGUGUUCACAAGGCCAGUUUCUGAUCGUCCGCCCCGAGGCUGAGGACCAGUAGGCAGCUCCCAAGAUGGGUGAAAGGAAAGGGGUCAACAAGUACUAUCCUCCAGACUUCAACCCUGAGAAGCAUGGCUCUCUCAACCGAUACCACAACAGCCACCCGCUUCGGGAGCGGGCUCGGAAGCUGUCACAGGGCAUCCUCAUCAUCCGAUUCGAAAUGCCAUAUAACAUCUGGUGCGAUGGCUGCAAGAACCACAUCGGCAUGGGUGUUCGUUACAAUGCAGAAAAGAAGAAGGUGGGCAAUUACUACACAACCCCGAUCUACAGGUUCCGGAUGAAAUGCCACCUCUGUGUCAACUACAUCGAGAUGCAGACGGACCCCGCCAACUGCGACUACGUGAUCGUGAGUGGCGCCCAGCGCAAGGAGGAGCGCUGGGACAUGGCGGACAAUGAGCAGGUGCUGACCACAGGUGAGCGCCACCCACUUACCUGCCUGGGGGCCCUGGCCCUGAGUCUGCGCUGGGGCCCCCAAAGCCCAGCCGAGCUCUGAUCGUUGCAGAGCAUGAGAAGAAGCAGAAGCUGGAGACGGACGCCAUGUUCCGGCUGGAGCAUGGCGAGGCCGACCGCAGCACACUCAAGAAGGCGCUGCCCACACUGAGCCACAUCCAGGAGGCCCAGAGCGCCUGGAAGGACGACUUCGCCCUCAACAGCAUGCUGCGGAGAAGGUUCCGGGAAAAGAAAAAAGCCAUCCAGGAGGAGGAGGAGAGAGACCAGGCCUUGCAGGCCAAGGCGAGCCUGACCAUCCCGCUGGUGCCCGAGACGGAAGAUGACCGCAAGCUGGCGGCUCUGCUGAAGUUCCACACCCUGGACUCCUACGAGGACAAGCAGAAACUCAAGCGGACCGAGAUCAUCAGCCGCUCCUGGUUCCCCUCUGCCCCCGGAUCCGCCUCCAGCAGCAAGGUCAGCGGCGUCCUGAAGAAGCUGGCACAGAGCCGCAGAACCGCGCUUGCCACCUCCCCCAUCACCGUCGGGGACCUGGGCAUCGUGCGGCGGAGGUCUCGGGACGUCCCGGAGAGCCCCCAGCAUGCGGCCGACACCCCCAAGUCUGGGGAACCGCGGGUACCAGAGGAGGCUGCCCAGGACCGGCCCAUGUCCCCCGGAGACUGUCCUCCGGAAACAACUGAGACCCCCAAGUGCAGCAGCCCGAGGGGGCAGGAAGGGAGCCGUCAGGACAAGCCCCUGUCGCCAGCAGGCUCCUCCCAGGAGGCAGCUGACACCCCCGACACGCGGCACCCCUGCAGUCUCGGCUCCUCCCUCGUGGCGGACUACUCCGACUCGGAGAGUGAGUGAGCGAUCCCCAUCCUGGAGACUGGACCCGCUCUAGAGGCCCGGACACACCCAGGAGGCCCCUCACAGACUGCAGACCCCCGGCUCGCCCACCAGCCCUGGGAGAGCUCAGAUGCCGCAUCCUCCCCAGACCGCGCCUUCCUGCAACCGUGGAGUUAUUUAUUUGGUCCUGGUGAGGGUGUUUGUGCCUUGUGAGACUCCGUACAUUAAAGACCUGUCUCUUC